AGAGAGUGAAAAAUCUCCUUAGAAAAGACUUUUCAGUUAAUGACAGUGGUGAUUCUAGGAUUAUCUUAAGUUCACUGUGGUCUUUUCUUUAGAGGUGGUAGAAUGCCCAACUGUUCCAGUUUGUUCUGGAUAGGGGAGUGUCCCAGGAUGAAGGACUUUCGGUGCUAAAACCAGAGAAGUCCUGGGUAAAUUGGGACAAGUUGGUCACCUAGAUCAUGGUGAUAUUUGACUCCUUUCCUGUUUUCAUCUGAUCAGGUAGGCUCCUCCAGAAGACAAAAAUAGCAUUCAAAGAAAAUUAUUAAAGGCCUGCUGAUGAACUGACAUCACCAUCAUCAUUUUAGUAAUAAUAAUAAUACUGUAAUAAUAAGCCAUAUUUAGAAGGAAACUAAAUAUCUUUCUAAGGAAAUUUCUAGCAAACCAAGACAAACACUACUGGGAUGAUUUUCACAAAAGAUUUACUCUUUGGAUGGUAAGCAAGCACUAAGAAAGUAGCUAUUCCAAUGGGGCAGGAGGAAGAAAAGAGAAGCUGGGGUGCUUGACAUAGUUCAGAUACUACAAAUCUGGUGCUCCUGAUCUACAGAAGGAAGUGUGGACAUAGACCCACACUGGGUGUGAGAGUAACAGGAAGAGGUGCAAGAGAGAGGUGAUUCCCCUCUAGAAAGUUUGGGGCAAGCCUGGAGGGGAUGCUGGCUUUGUGGGCUGUUGCCAGGAUAGUUGCUACCCACCUGUGCUCUGGCCUGAACCUGGCUGAGUCAUCACCCAGAAUGCUGUGACAAGUGGGAGUAAUUAUAGCCCAGGAGGACAUGGAAGCAUCAAGUAAUUACAGCCGAGGGGGACACGCCCUGGGCUAUGGCGCUGCUGUGCACAGAGCACGAGGCAAGGUACAGGCAGGUGUGGGCAAAAGGUAUAGAUGCUUCAAAGUAUUAUUAAAAAUGUGUGGAUCCCCAUGAAGCUCUACUAUACUCAAGUUUACCAGGAUAUUUGGGUAGGAAUGGGGCUGAUGAGCCUCAUCAUUUAUAAAAUCCAGAGUGCUAAUAAAAGAAGUAAAGCUUUGAAAUCUCCGGUGCCUGCUCACAGUCAUCACUAACCAGCUUUACCUGGAGUACACAUGAAAUGAAACAUCAGUCAGCUUGUAAAUUUAAGUAAGCUGUGUUAGACUGUACACUUGUUUAAGUAUCGCUUACUUCAUGGCAUGAAUAAAUGGAUCUGUGAAAUUCACUGAAAAAAAAAAGA